UUUUUUUUUUUUAAGACAGAGUCUCACUCUGUCGCCCAGGCUGGAGUCCAGUGGCACGAUCUCGGCUCACUGCAAGCGCCUUGGCUACAGGAACUGCCAUGUGGCGUCAGAACCCUGAAGAAGUUCCCACCUGGGUUCACACCAUUCUCCUGCCUCAGCCUCCUGAGUAGCUGGGAUUACGGGCGCCCGCCACCACGCCCGGCUAAUUUUUUUCAAAGUAGUUACGCUUGCAAACUCUAA